AUUACGUAUUCAGAUACUGCUUUGCUUCAUCCUCUCUAAAAUUUAACACCGAGGAGUUUAAGAAAUGAAGAUAAGGAACUCGAAUUAUUUUUAAACUUUGGAUCAAUGUAAAGGCAAUCUAAUAUUUGGAAAAUACUUGCAAUGUUGUUCUCCUGGCGAGAAGAUCCUGGAGCCCAGUGCCUGCUGCUUUCUCUUCUGCUCCUCGCAGCCUCGGAGGUGGGGAGCGGCCAGCUCCACUACUCCGUCUCUGAGGAGGCCAAGCAUGGCACCUUCGUGGGCCGCAUCGCGCAGGACCUGGGGCUGGAGCUGGCGGAGCUGGUGCCGCGCCUGUUCCGGGUGGCGUCCAAAAGACACGGGGACCUUCUGGAGGUAAAUCUGCAGAAUGGCAUUUUGUUUGUGAAUUCUCGGAUAGACCGCGAGGAACUGUGCGGGCGGAGCGCGGAGUGCAGCAUCCACCUGGAGGUGAUCGUGGACAGGCCGCUGCAGGUUUUCCAUGUGGAGGUGGAAGUGAAGGACAUUAAUGACAACGCGCCAGUUUUUCCAAUGGCUGUAAAGAAUCUGUUUAUUUCCGAAUCCCGACAGCCUGGCUCUCGGUUUUCGCUAGAGGGCGCAUCAGAUGCAGAUAUCGGAACAAAUUCGUUGUUGACUUACAGUCUUGAUUCCACUGAAUAUUUUACCUUGGACGUUAAAAGAAAUGAUGAGGAAAUUAAAUCCCUUGGACUCGUGUUGAAAAAAAAUUUAAAUCGAGAGGACACUCCUAAGCAUUAUUUACUAAUAACAGCAAUUGAUGGUGGGAAACCAGAGCUCACUGGCACGACUCAACUAAAGAUCACUGUUUUAGAUGUAAACGACAACGCCCCAGCGUUUGAGAGGACGAUCUAUAAAGUCAGAUUACUCGAAAAUGCACCAAAUGGUACCCUAGUGGUGACCGUUAACGCCACCGAUUUGGAUGAAGGAGUAAAUAAGGAUAUCGCGUAUUCUUUCAAUACGGACAUGUCAGCAGAUAUUCUGUCAAAAUUCCAUUUAGAUCCAGUCAAUGGACAAAUCAGUGUAAAGGGUAACAUAGAUUUCGAGGAAAGUAAGUCAUAUGAAAUCCAGGUAGAAGCCACGGAUAAAGGAAAUCCCCCAAUGUCAGAUCACUGCACAGUUCUACUCGAAAUUGUGGACAUCAAUGAUAAUGUACCUGAGUUAGUUAUUCAAUCACUAUCUUUACCUGUAUUAGAAGACUCUCCACUUAGCACAGUCAUCGCUCUGAUCAGCGUGUCCGACCGCGACUCAGGAGUCAAUGGACAGGUCACCUGCUCGCUGACGCCCCACGUCCCCUUCAAGCUGGUGUCCACCUUCAAGAAUUACUACUCAUUGGUGCUGGACAGCCCUCUGGACCGCGAGAGCGUGUCGGCCUAUGAGCUGGUGGUGACUGCUCGGGACGGGGGCUCGCCUUCACUGUGGGCCACGGCCAGCGUGUCCGUGGAGGUGGCCGACGUGAACGACAAUGCGCCGGCAUUCUCGCAGUCCGAGUACACGGUGUUCGUGAAGGAGAACAACCCGCCGGGCUGCCACAUCUUCACGGUGUCUGCGCGGGACGCGGACGCGCAGGAGAACGCCCUGGUGUCCUACUCGCUGGUGGAACGGCGGGUGGGGGAGCGCGCGCUGUCGAGCUACGUGUCGGUACACGCGGAGAGCGGCAAGGUGUACGCGCUGCAGCCGCUGGACCACGAGGAGCUAGAGCUGCUGCAGUUCCAGGUGAGUGCGCGCGAUGCGGGCGUGCCGCCUCUGGGCAGCAACGUGACGCUGCAGGUGUUCGUGCUGGACGAGAACGACAACGCGCCGGCACUGCUGAUGCCUCGGGUGGGUGGCAUCGGUGGCGCAGUGAGCGAGCUGGUGCCGCGGUCAGUGGGUGCGGGCCACGUGGUAGCGAAGGUGCGCGCAGUGGAUGCAGACUCAGGCUACAACGCGUGGCUUUCGUAUGAGCUGCAGCCUGGGACCGGCGGUGCGCGCAUCCCGUUUCGCGUGGGGCUGUACACGGGAGAGAUCAGCACGACCCGUGCCCUGGACGAGGUGGACGCCCCGCGCCAUCGCCUACUGGUGCUGGUGAAGGACCACGGUGAACCCUCAUUGACCGCCACGGCCACUGUGCUGGUGUCGCUGGUGGAGAGUGGCCAGGCACCCAAGGCCUCGUCCCAGGCGUCCGCUGGCGCCACGGGCCCGGAAGCUGCACUGGUGGAUGUCAACGUGUACUUGAUCGUCGCCAUCUGCGCGGUGUCCAGUCUGUUGGUGCUCACACUGCUGCUAUAUACUGCUCUGCGGUGCUCCGCGCCGCCAACCGAAGGCGACUGUGGGCCGGGCAAGCCCACGCUGGUGUGCUCCAGCGCGGUGGGGAGCUGGUCAUACUCGCAGCAGAGGCAGCAGAGGGUGUGCUCUGGAGAGGGGUUGCCCAAGACCGACCUCAUGGCUUUUAGCCCUAGCCUUCCUCCUUGUCCAAUUAGCCGGGAUAGAGAGGAGAAACAGGAUGUGGACGUUGAUCUCUCAGCCAAACCACGACAGCCCAACCCUGACUGGCGUUACUCUGCCUCCCUGAGAGCAGGCAUGCACAGCUCUGUGCACCUAGAGGAGGCUGGCAUUCUACGGGCUGGUCCAGGAGGGCCUGAUCAGCAGUGGCCAACAGUAUCCAGUGCAACACCAGAACCAGAGGCAGGAGAAGUGUCCCCUCCAGUCGGUGCGGGUGUCAACAGCAACAGCUGGACCUUUAAAUACGGACCAGGCAACCCCAAACAAUCCGGUCCCGGUGAGUUGCCCGACAAAUUCAUUAUCCCAGGAUCUCCUGCAAUCAUCUCCAUCCGGCAGGAGCCUACUAACAGCCAAAUUGACAAAAGUGACUUCAUAACCUUCGGCAAAAAGGAGGAGACCAAGAAAAAGAAGAAAAAGAAGAAGGGUAACAAGACCCAGGAGAAAAAAGAGAAAGGGAACAGCACGACUGACAACAGUGACCAGUGAGGUCCUCAAAUGGAAACAAGCCACUUAGCCAGUUUUUGUAAUAAUGGCAAAUCUCUCCCAUGUAGCAAUUCCCUGCUCCUUUUUCCUAUCUACAUGAGCCCUCUUAGAGACCUCAGAAAUCUGCAGAAAGUUCCCUGUGUCUGUCUAGAACGCAUUUAACAGGUUUUGUCGUAAAAGCUUUACUAAGUCUGGUGUUAACUCUUUCUCUCCACUCUGGCUUGUUUUCAGAACCUAAAAAGCAGACCCAAGUUUCCUUUCUCCUCCGCCGCAAAGGAGAGGCUUCCCAGCCCCGCCAGUGAGAGGUUGGACUCUCUGCCCUGUGCUCCGGGGAUCCUGUCUUGAUGACACUUGCAGGGCAGGCUGAAAAGUUUUGAGAUUGAGCAGCUUGGGAGUUUGUGGCCACUGGGUAUGUGUGGCUACCGCGGGUAUGCGAGUGCCAGAUAUUGGCUGAGACGAGCCAGCUUAGACUAAUUGGUACAAGGAAGGCAAGAAAACAAAGACAAAUAAACAGCGGAAGUUAUCAGUAUGGAGGGGAAGUGUAAACUUAAAGGGACCAGACUUUCUAAAUCUUACAACUCAAGAGGUGGCAGCCACCCUCUAGGAGACAAAACUACCCCCACUGACAAGGCUUUAGGAGACCCUAAAGUCUGUUGGCUGUGACGUCAUUAUACCUAAAAUCUGCAUCAUACCUGCAAGCCAACAGUUCAGUGUUUUAACAGAGAACCACCCUGGGAAACAGAAGCAGAUCUGAUGUGUUUCCUAUACAUGUCCUGUGCUCACUUUAUUAAAAAUUCUUUUGCACACAAUGUUUAUGAAAAGGCCAGAUCCUUUUCCAAUACUUAUGCAAAAGCAAAAGAAAACCCCGACACCUCACCUUUCGCUGUUUGUUGUUUCAUAGAUUUAUUUAAAAAAAGAGAAAGUCUAUAGCUAUAAAUCUUUAAAGAGAAAUAUGAAUACAAUUCCCCUAAACUCUCCUCAAAAGAGAAUUCAGUCUACAGCCAUUUAAAUGAUCAUUGCUGCUACAGAAGUGCUUUAAGAGAAUUGCCUGAAACAUCUGUAUUAUAUCGGCCACCUGCCAAUCACAGCUUUACUCUUUCAGGUCACUCUGGGGCUGCCUCUUGCAUGUAUUACUAAAUAAAAUGAUCUCUCUUUCUCUCUCUCUCUCUCUUUUCUAAGAAACAAUUAUGUGCACUUUGAUACACAACCUUCUCUAACCAACUAUAUAUCAAGACCCAAAAAUUGAAGAAAAAUAUUGUUUUCUCAUACAGUGAGCAGAUUUUUCAAUCUACUAAUUCUGUGACUUGUCUUGGUGUGCUAGCCUACACCUUCUCUUUGGUUUAGUUUUCCUUUUCUAUAACACUCUGAAUUGCUAAUCUUACUAACACCUAUGAUGUUACCUGAAAUCAAUCUCCCAUAUGUAUGCUGUAUGCUAUGCUAAGACUCCUGAAAUAUACUUACUCUGUGCUUGUGUAUGUGAAUGUUAAUGCAACUAUUACCUAGAGUGAACUUUAAGCUUUAUUGUUGAAUGUAAUUCCAUUAUAUUUCCUUUUGUACACCUGUGAAAAAGUGGAGUAGUGUUUUUUUAACCAUUGUUAAUCAGCUUUUGUGUAUGAAAGACACAGUAAAAUUUCUUUCUUAAAUCAAGAUACUGGUGAUUCAAGGAAUUUUAUUUAUGGUCCAGCCAAGAGCCAUCUCGUGCCAAGACUUCUGCUGGCAAGGGAAUGGAUAAAGCUGUUUUGUUCUAGUAACAAUUUUGGAAUGAAUACUGACAAUAUUCCAUGAGGGUGUGCAAGCACAAAUUUUACCAAUCUGACCUCUUUGAAGUUGCAGAAUGCUUUGAAAUUCUAAUGGUAUCUGAAAUAUCAGCUCAUAGAAAGUAACAAAAUUUGCUGUCACCUUAAAUAAGACAUUUUAAUUUUGUUAUAAUGUACAAUUUAGAAGUUUGAUUAAUUAUAUUAUCUAUUUAGGCAUUAAUAUAAAAGAGGUAGGAGUCUGUUAUUUAAAAAAAGCAUUAAAUUUAAAAAAAAACUGUCUUGUCUACUUUUAGCUUCAUUCUCCCAUAUUUUGAAGGGUGUGUAACUUCAGCUCUGCAGGAUUGCAUGGGGUAAAACUUGUUACCAACACAUGUGAACCAUUGCUACAUUGUAGGUUGUGAUCAUUUUGCCCCACUGAAGCCCAUGUAUCUGACCUUACGUGCCUUUUGAACUAGGAGAAUCGGGCUAAUUUAUUAAUGAUGAUAAUUAUAAUGUAUCUGUACAGCACUUUUUACAUUUGCGAAGUGCUUUCCAAUCCAUGUUAGUUACUAGUUAUUACAGCUGUAAGGAUAAAACACGUCAUGUGGAUUCAUUUUGAAUUGGUGCUAUUGGUAUUUCCUCUGUUAUUGCUAAUAAAUGAAAAUGGUGGUAUGAAA